ACUUUCAACAUGGAGAGUGGAGCAGGAAAGCACUGGACUGAGGAGGAGGUUAAAGCUUUGCUAAGUGUCUGGGCAGAAAAAAAUAUACGAAAACAACUUUAUGGAACACUAAGAAAUAAAGGAAUAUUUAUUUACAUUGCUAAAAGGCUGCAAUCAUUAGGAGUAUACAGAGACUGGAAACAGUGCUGGGCUAAGUACAAAAAUCUCAAAUAUGAAUAUAGAACAGUUAAAUAUGCCCAUAACUCUGGAGACAGCUCUAAAACUAUGAAGUUCUUCCAUGAUUUGGAUGUAAUCCUGCAGUAUGAACCUGCCACACAAUUUACAGAGGAAGAUGCAAAUGGCAGGUACCUGGAAACGCUCAGCCCAAGUACAGCCCCAGAGACCACUGAAGCAGAAUUUUUAUUGGUGUGUGAUACACGGAAGAAGGGAAGAAAACGAAAGUGCCUUUUCCACUGUUGGGAUCAACCUCAUGCAAGUGAGCCUCUGCCUACAGUUUUAGGAUUCAUGCUGUGGAAUGAGCAACUUAAGAAAAAAUUAUCUGAAGAGGUUGGAGAGAGAGCUUUUCUGUUUCACUACCAUCUGUAUGUUUGGUCCAGACUCUUUUCUAUGGACGUAAAUCUGGACUCUAAACCAGGUAAAAUGUCAAUUGCAUCAGUAGAUAAGGAAGAUGUCUCAGGAAAUCCUUUACUUCUGGUUUCUCAUGUCAGACCAAUGGAACUAGCAAAUGAAGGAGGAAAGCACUGGACUGUGCCAGAAGUCAGGGCUCUAAUAGACAUCUGGUCUGAUAAAAGCAUACAACGACAACUAGAGGGAACAGUGAGAAAUAAGAGGAUAUUUCAACAAAUUGCAGCCAAGCUUCAGAAAUUUGGAAUAGACAGAGACUGGAAACAGUGCAGAACAAAAUACAAAAACCUAAAACACGAAUACAAGAUCGUAAGAACAGCUCAAGAUCUAGGCAUGACUAAGAGUAUGAAAUUUUUUACUGAGUUGGAUGCUAUUCUGGGACCCAAUAAAACAGAAAAAUCACGAGACCAGGAAUCCCAAGAUGGAGAACAUGUCACAGAAUGUGCCAACGUAAAAAUGGGAGAGGACCAGACAGUACAUCCAGAUAGAGAAGAACUUAUUACUAAAACUUCAGAAAACCGAAGACUUACAAAUGUGAAAAAAGAAAGCUCAGACAUAGAAUUAUUUGAAGGUCACAACAAAAGCCAAGGAACUUUGAGCUUCAAGAGAAAAGCACAUGAAGAUGAACCAGUGUCUAAAUCUCUUAAGAAAAGUGCUCCUGAGAUCAUUACAAAUCAGUUUCCUCAAAGCGUAAUAACAGAACCAAAAGAUUCUACAGAAUGUUUCUGCAGACAGAAAACCCAACUUCAUCAGAGUUCUGCCUCGCUUCCCGGCGCGGUCGCAGCCCUCAGCCCACUUAGGAUAAUGGCGACAGCUGAGGUACUGAACAUUGGUAAAAAAUUAUAUGAGGGUAAAACAAAAGAAGUCUACGAAUUGUUAGACAGUCCAGGAAAAGUCCUCCUGCAGUCCAAGGACCAGAUUACAGCAGGAAAUGCAGCUAGAAAAAACCACCUGGAAGGAAAAGCUGCAAUCUCAAAUAAAAUCACCAGUUGUAUUUUUCAGUUAUUACAGGAAGCAGGUAUUAAAACUGCCUUCACCAGAAAAUGUGGGGAGACAGCUUUCAUUGCACCGCAGUGUGAAAUGAUUCCAAUUGAAUGGGUUUGCAGAAGAAUAGCAACUGGUUCUUUUCUCAAAAGAAAUCCUGGUGUCAAGGAAGGAUAUAAGUUUUACCCACCUAAAGUGGAGUUGUUUUUCAAGGAUGAUGCCAAUAAUGACCCACAGUGGUCUGAGGAACAGCUGAUUGCUGCAAAAUUUUGCUUUGCUGGACUUCUUAUAGGCCAGACUGAAGUGGAUAUCAUGAGUCAUGCUACACAGGCUAUAUUUGAAAUACUGGAGAAAUCCUGGUUGCCCCAGAAUUGUACACUGGUUGAUAUGAAGAUUGAAUUUGGUGUUGAUGUAACCACCAAAGAAAUUGUUCUUGCUGAUGUUAUUGACAAUGAUUCCUGGAGACUCUGGCCAUCAGGAGAUCGAAGCCAACAGAAAGACAAACAGUCUUAUCGGGACCUCAAAGAAGUAACUCCUGAAGGGCUCCAAAUGGUAAAGAAAAACUUUGAGUGGGUUGCAGAGAGAGUAGAGUUGCUUUUGAAAUCAGAAAGUCAGUGCAGGGUUGUAGUGUUGAUGGGCUCUACUUCUGAUCUUGGUCACUGUGAAAAAAUCAAGAAGGCCUGUGGAAAUUUUGGCAUUCCAUGUGAACUUCGAGUAACAUCUGCGCAUAAAGGACCAGAUGAAACUCUGAGGAUUAAAGCUGAGUAUGAAGGGGAUGGCAUUCCUACUGUAUUUGUGGCAGUGGCAGGCAGAAGUAAUGGUUUGGGACCAGUGAUGUCUGGGAACACUGCAUAUCCAGUUAUCAGCUGUCCUCCCCUCACACCAGACUGGGGAGUUCAGGAUGUGUGGUCUUCUCUUCGACUACCCAGUGGUCUUGGCUGUUCAACCGUACUUUCUCCAGAAGGAUCAGCUCAAUUUGCUGCUCAGAUAUUUGGGUUAAGCAACCAUUUGGUAUGGAGCAAACUGCGAGCAAGCAUUUUGAACACAUGGAUUUCCUUGAAGCAGGCUGACAAGAAAAUCAGAGAAUGUAAUUUAUAAGAAAGAAUGCCAUUGAAUUUUUUAGGGGAAAAACUACAAAUUUCUAAUUUAGCUGAAGGAAAAUCAAGCAAGAUGAAAAGGUAAUUUUAAAUUAGAGAACACAAAUAAAAUGUAUUAGUGAAUAAAUGCUUCUCUAGAUCCAUAUUAAUAAACAUGAGCAUCUAACCCCUCCUUUCUUAGGCUAGACACCAAGAUAUUUCAGCCAGCCUUUAUCAUUCCUCUUACUUUAUCCUUUUUCCUUAAGUAUUGGUGGUCACUACUAUUGAGUUUCUUCCUUAACACUGAUUAAAUGAUCUUAACUCCCUCAGCUAAAACUGGCAUUACUGACUCCCAGCUAUAUUUCUCCAGACUUGCAUUUUUUUUUUUUUUUUUGAGACAGGGUCUCACUGUCGCCCAGGCUGGAGUGCAGUGGCGUGAUCUCAGUUCACUGCUGCUUUCCCUCCUGGGCUCAAGCAGUUCUCCCACCUCAGCCUCUCGACUAACAGGGACUAUAAUCUUGCAGCACCAUGCCGAGCUAAUUUUAUUUUUUGUAGAGAUGAGCUCUCACUAUGUCACCCAGGUUCGUCUCAAACUCCUGAACCCUAGUAAUUCUCCUAUCUCAGCCUCCCAAAGUGCUAGGGUUACAGACAUGAGCCACUGUGCCUGUCUAGACUUGUACUUUCAACUGUCCAUUUCUCCCUGUCUGUCCCAUGGGCACUCAUGAAAAAACAGAAUGCUCCCAACUUUAUUCAUCUUCCAAGCCUGUAGCUCUUGGUAUACUCACUGUUGCAAGUCAGAAGCUUGAUUUCAUCAUUGAUGUUUUUCUCACGUUUCACAUCUCACUCAUCACCAAGUCAUGUUGGUGUUAAUUUCUGAUUAACCCUUGAAUUUACCGUCUUCUCAUCCUCUGUACAAAAGCCUCAAGUGAGGGUCAAAUUCAACAUUAUCCUGAUCUAGACAGCCCCCAUUCUCAAUCCACCCUUUUCCAAGUUGAUUGCCCAAGGACUUCUAACAAUAAACUCUCUUUUGCACCACAGACUUCUUUGAAAAUAUACAUGCUGUUGACCCUCUCUGUAGAAAACCGCACACAUAAAACUUACCAACAGAUUUCAUUGGUUCUUGGGUUCUCCCGAAGCCUAUCCAUGGUUUAUAGAUUAAGAAUUGAUGAGGUAGCUGGGCACAGUGGCUCACACCUACGAUCACAGCACUUCGGGAGGCUGAAGCAAGCAGAUCACUUGAGGUCAGGAGUUUGAGACCAGCCUGGCCAACAUGGUGAAACCCUGUCUCUACUAAAAAUACAAAAAGUAGCCAGCCGUGAUGACAGGCACCUGUAAUCCCAGCUACUCGGGAGGCUGAGGCAUGAGAAUUGCUUGAACCCGGGAGGCGGAGGUUGCAGUGAGCCUAGAUCAUGCCACUGCACUCCAACCUGGGCAGCAGAGCAAGACUCUGUCUCAAAAGGGGAAAAAAAAAAUUGCUGAUGUGACCCAUGAAGGGAACUCAUUUUCCUCGUAAUUUUGGACUGCCACACAUUGGUACCUUUAGUUCUCUGAAGGCCCACGUUUUUAUCAUUAAGACCUAUUUGUUAGCUAGUAGAGCUUUAUGUUCGCUGUCCAUGAAACCUUCUGUAACCACAGUGACUACAAGUAGUUCUUUCUCUAUUGAAUUAUUAGGUCCAGAAUAGAAGAUGUCAUUGUACACUUUAUUUCCCUCACACUGUGUUAUGCUCUGAUGUGCUAUGCUUAGCUAUCUGUCAGAGAUUAGUAAAUUAUAAAACUCAUGUGUACUACUUAAGUUUAUAUCUUAUGCUAGUUUAUAAGAACAAUUAAAAGGACUUAGAAGAUUAACUUUGGUUUCAUGGUCUCUGAAGUCACUGACUGCUAUUUCAGCUUGUUUACCCUUACCUAGCAUUAAGACUCCAUCUACUUCUGUGCAGUAUAUGAAAAUUUUUAAACUUUCAUUUAGACUGGUGGAUAGGACUGACCAUUACAAAUUGUCGUUAUCAAUUUUUUUUCCUUUUUUUUUUUAAGAGCCAAGUUCUCACUGUCUCCCAGGCUGGAGUGCAGUGGCAUGAUUAUGGCUCCCUGCAGCCUUGAACUCCUGGACUCAAGCUGCAGCCUCUCGAGUAGCUGGGUGCAUGUGCUACCACACCCAAUUAUGAAUUUCAUCAUUAGUUUCUUAGUAGAGUCCACAUGUCCUCAGUAGUAAGUUCAUCAGUGCUAAAUAUUUGAAGGUAUUUCUACUGUUUUGUAAAAGUAACUUAAGCCUACCUGGUCUGCUAUCUUUUGAGUAUUUAUACUUUCUACGGGCUUGUAGGUAAACAUAAAAAGAGAAAAAAUAUCCCAAUAAUACAGUUUUUAACCUUUUAUGAUAAAGACAUGCUUAGAAUUGCUGUUAAGCUUUCUGAGAUUUAACCACUGAAACUAAGUAAAAGACAAAGCACUUAGGUAAAGCUUCAUUCAGUAUCCAUUCACCCAAUACUGGUUUGAUUCUAGGGCCUAGGAAAAUAGGACUGAGCAAAGCCCUUGUCCAGAUGGAACUUAUGUUUUAGAGGGGAAAACAAACCAUAAAAAGGUAAACAGUAUAAAAUCAGGAAAGGAUAAAUGUAUAUGAAGAAUCAAAAUGAGGACGGUGAUGGGGAUAAGAGGGGAAGGUUUUUGAGGAGAGCAGAGCAAUGAUGUAAAAGCAAGACACACAGAUAGGGAAAUAGCUUUCCAUACUAAGGGAAUGGGAAAUAAAGCUGAGUUUUGCCUUGAGGACCUCCAAACAUGAGAAUUGCUAGAGCUCUGUGAACAAGGAUGAGAGUGGAAGACAAUAUAAGCAAAGGCUACAUCACUUAGGGCCUAUAGGCCACACUGAAGUGUGACAGGAAAAACUCAGUUUGAGCAGAGGCUUGACAUACUUAACAUAUUUAAAGGUUCUCUGGCUGUUGUGUGGACAAGAGGAGAAGCAGAGAUUAGUUAAGAGGCUAUUGUAGCCCAGGUGAGGGAUGAUGUAUGAUCUUCAACAUGUCUAAUUUUUUUGUGCCUCAAUUUCAUGAAAUGAAAAUGCGACUAAUACCACCUCAUAAAGUUGUGAGAAUUACAUGAGUCAAUAUAUGUAAGGCCCAUCAUGGCACACAAAUGUGUUAUGUAAUAUCCAUUUGGCAGACUGAAGAACAACAGUAUGAAUGGAAUUCAUUCACCAUGAGAAUUACCUGGAAUUCUCUGGGCAUGGUAGCUCAUGCCUGUAAUCCCAGCACUUUGGGUGGCCGAGGCAGGUGGAUCACCUGAGAUCAGGAGUUCGAGACCAGCCUGACCAACAUGGAGAAACCCAGUCUCUAAUAAAAAUACAAAACUAGCCGGGCAUGGUGGCACAUUCCUGUAAUCCCAGCGACUCAGGAGGCUGAGGCAGGAGAAUCGCUUGAACCUGGGAAGCGGAGGUUGUGGUGAGCCGAGGUUGCGCCAUUGUACUCCAGCCUGGGCAACAAGAGCAAAACUCUGUUUCAAAAAAAAAGAAAGAAAGAAAAUUACCUGGAAUUCAAUAUUGCCAUCGGCUGAUUUAAUUUCUAAUAUGAAGAAAGGGGCAGUGUGAUGUGCCACGGAGCAUCCACAACCUGCCAUUUCAGCCCAGCCAACCUUAGAAAGCCAUUGAAAAGAGUUGUUUUUAAUGGUGUUUUUACAUCCAGCUUCCCACACCUCAAAUACUUGGGGUGGAAUUGUUAAUCUCACAUUGCAGUACAAUGAAAAUAGUGGAAUGGAAAUCAAGUUAUAAAAUGGAGCUAAAUAUUUCUUCUGCUUGCCUCUGAGUUGAUAAGAUACCAUAAGAUACUGUACAUGAGGCUGGGCGCGGUGGCUCACGUCUUAUUUCUUCUGCUUGCCUCUGAGUUGACAAGAUACCAUAAGAUACUGUACAUGAGGCUGGGUGCAGUGGCUCACGCCUGUAAUCCCAGCACUUUGGGAGGGUGAGGUGGGCAGAUCACCUGAGGUCGGGAGUUCAAGACCAGCCUGACUGACAUGGAGAAACCCCCUCUUUACUAAAAAUACAAAAUUAGCCAGGCAUGGUGGUGCAUGCCUAUAAUUCCAACUACUCGGGAGGCUGAGGCAGGAGAAUCGCUUGAACCUGGAAGGCAGAGGUUGUGGUGAGCUGAGAUCGAACCAUUGCACUCCAGCCUGGGCAACAAGAGCGAAAAUCUGUCGCCAAAAAAAAAAAAAAAAAGAUACUGUACAUGGAAGCUUCUCAGGCUAAAUCCAUUAAUAUAAAAAUACAUUGUGGAUACUGAUGAGAUGGCUAAUUCUGUCAACUUGACUAGGCUACGGGAUGCCUUGAUAGCUGGUCAAACAACAUUUCUAGGUACAUCUGUGAUGGUGUUUCUGGAAGAGACUAGCACUUGAAUCAGUAGACUUGAGUAAAGAAGACUGCCUUCACCCAUGUGGGUGAGCGUCAUCUAAUCCAUUGAGGGCCUGAAUAGAACAAAAAAGGGGAAGAAGGGUGAACUGCUGGGACAUCCAUUUCGUGCCCCCAGAUGUUGGUGCUCCUGGUCCUCAGGCCUUCAGACUAGGACUUAACGUUAUUGCCUCCCCUGAUUCUCAAGCCCUCGGGUUUGGAACUACACUGGCUUUCCUGGGCCUUCAGCCUGCAGAAGGCAGACUGUGGGACUUCACCUCCAUUUUGCAGAGCCAAUUUCUCAUAAUCUGUACAUAUCCUAUUGGUUCUGUAUUUUUUAGAGAACAAAUACAGCCUAUUAUGUAUAUAUAAGACCCUGGGAAUGCAAAGAUGAACAAAAUUAACCUUCUGCUCUCAAUGAAUCUUGGAAGUCUCCAGAGGCAGACAAUUUCAAAACACCGUAUAUAGUCUUAAUAUGGAAUUAACAAUAGGGUAUUGUGAAUACACAAAAGUAGGAAGGACUCUGAUCUCUAGAAAACAAUUGUAUACUGUGAAUGAAAAAGACUAAUUCUCCACAGUCUAUACUCAAUCUCUCUUACCUUUCCAUAAUUUUCUUCAGCAAACUUAUUACCACCAAACAUAGUACAUGUUUAUUUAUUACCCAUCUCUCCCAACUAGAAAAUAAAUGUAUUACACUGG